UUGUUUUUUUUUGUUUUUUUUUUUUUUGAGACAGGUCAUUCUGUCACCCAGGCUGGAGCUGCAAUGGCAUGAUCUCGGUUCACUGCAGCCUCCGUCUCCUGGGAUCAAGCAAUUCUCCUACCUCAGCCUCCUGAGUUGCUGGGAUUACAGGGGUGCACCACCACGCCUGGCUAAUUUUUACACUUUUAGUAGAGACAGGGUUUCACCAUGUUGGCCAGGCUGGUCUCGAACUCCUGACCUUAGGUGAUCCACCCAACCUGGCCUCCCAAAGUGCUGGGAUUACAGGCGUGAGCCACUGCGCCCGGCUUGGGUAAGCAAGUUAAUAAACCUCUCUUAACUUCAGUUUCUCCCUGAGUAAAAAUGGAGAUGCAAAUAUUUAACUCACAGGCUUAAAAACAAUGUAAUGAGAUAAUGAUUGUAUUAUUUUUUAAAACUGUAUGUUAGAUUCAGGGAGUACAUGUGCAGGCUUGUUACAAGGAUAUAUUGUGUAAUGAUGAGCUUUGAGCUUCUAGUGUACACAUCACCCAAAUAGUGCACACCGUACUCAAUAGGUAAUUUUUCAACCCUCACUCCCCUCUUUCCCCACUUUUGUAGUCUAAAAUGUCUACUAUUUCCAUCUUUUUCCAUCUUUAUGUCCAUCAGUACUCAGAGAUAAUGAUUAAGAGACAAGCACAUAGUAAGUCCUUACUAAAUAUUUUUAAAAGAAUUCAUUAUAAAAGACACGAAAGGCUGGGCACGGUGCUCACUCCUGUAAUCCCAGCACUUUGGGAGGCCAAGGCGGGUGGAUCACCUGAGGUCAAGAGUUUGAGACCAGCCUGGCCAACACGUGGUAAAACCUCGUCCCUACUAAAAAUAAAAAAUUGGCUGGGCAUGGUGGCAGGCGCCUGUAAUCCCAGUUACUUGGGAGGCUGAGGCAGGAGAAUUGCUUGAAUCCAGGAGGUGGAGGUUGCAGUGAGGCGAGGUCACACCAUUGCAUUCUAGCCUGGGCAACAGAGCAAAAACUCCGUCUCAAUUAAAAAAAAAAAAAAAAAAGACAUGAAAGCAUUGUCCAGUAGAUAAUUUCAUUGGUCAUCUACAGUCUCUUGGAAUAUAGACAGCAGACAUUAAGAUUCCUGUUUUUCAAAGUGUUAUCUGAGGCACACAAAAAAACUAAAAGUCAGUAGCAGACAGACAAAGUCAGCAGCAUAACCAGGAGGCCUGGGAUGAGAUGUCCCUGCUGCUGUCUUUUGCAGACUGGGCUGCCUUUCUAAAUGGAGGUCAAGGGCACUCAGCUCCUGACUACCUCCAUGGGCUUACAAUUUGCCUUGGCACCUCCCCGGCUGAGAAAGCUGGGGCAUGGGAUAUUUAGUGAUUAACUCUGGCAGCAUGAGUAGAAGCACACAGAGGAAAGACUUCAACUCUAUUUUGUGUUUUCCACUUCUCAGUUUCUCUCCUCAUUUAAAAACAAAACCAAACCCUGUCUUAACUGUAGGAAGAGUUUUCUCCGUGUUGACUCCUUUUGGACAAAACAUUCCCUAUCCCAGGAACACCUUGUUUUGUAUUGUCAUGAGUUCAAACAGAUGCAAAGAAUGAAGAUAAGGGCAAAACCUACAUACUCCAACCACUGGAUCAUGUGGCACUCAGUAAAUACUACUUAAGGCUAAACCAGACAUUUAAAAGAGGAAACACAAGAACCUUUCAAAGCGCAGACCUUGUCGCUGACCUGGGCUAUGCAUUUCAAACUUAAAAGCAAGGUCAUUUUUAUUUUUUUAAAUUGUAGGAUCAGGUCAUGUGUUGUUUUCCCAGAGCCACGCUAAUAAGCUGCGCAUUUUUAGAGCUAUGGAAAGAACUCAAAAGCAAUGAGUGAAAAUGUAAGCCAUCAGUCUCCCUGCCCUCUCCUGAGUAUACAAACCCACUUGACUGCUGUCCAGUUUGAAGUAACUUCCAGCAAACCUGGUUGCUGUCUGCCCUCCCAACCCCCAGCACUGCCGAACAUUUACACCCGACAGUGUGAAUGCUGUGAAGAACACUUCUGCUUCCAUCUGCCCGCUUUCUUCCCAAAUGUUGGAAAGAAAGUACAAAAAUAAGAUUGCCAAGCAGAGGAAUAAAAAGGACGUAUAUUCCUUACGUCCCAAUUUAAAACAAUAUUAAAUUGCUCUAGCUGUUCGAUUCUAACACGUGUGGGAAGUGAAUUCUAUGUGAAAGAAGUGCCCAGCAGCAGUCAUGCUCUAGCCUAAGAAUGGGAGGGCUGGUCGGGAGGGCUGUGCCUGGAAACUUGUGCUCGUGUUAAAAGAACGUAGCUGUCCUUCUCUCUUUCCCUUUUAACUUUCAUCUCCACAUGGAGAAGGUGAUCACUCAAAAUAUGCAGCCAGACCUGUCUCCAGUACUGUCUGAAAUUCCAUUAACAGGAGAGAAGCUGCAGCAGCCAGACCUGUCUCCAGGACUGUCUGAAAUUCCAUUAACAGGAGAGAAGCUGCAGCAGCCAGACCUGUCUCCAGGACUGUCUGAAAUUCCAUUAACAGGAGAGAAGCUGCAGCAGCCAGACCUGUCUCCAGGACUGUCUGAAACUCCAUUAACAGGAGAGAAGCUGCAGCAGCCAGACCUGUCUCCAGGACUGUCUGAAACUCCAUUAACAGGAGAGAAGCUGCAGCAGCCAGACCUGUCUCCAGGAAUGUCUGAAACUCCAUUAACAGGAGAGAAGCUGCAGCAGCCAGACCUGUCUCCAGGACUGUCUGAAACUCCAUUAACAGGAGAGAAGCUGCAGCAGCCAGACCUGUCUCCAGGACUGUCUGAAACUCCAUUAACAGGAGAGAAGCUGCAGCAGCCAGACCUGUCUCCAGGACUGUCUGAAACUCCAUUAACAGGAGAGAAGCUGCAGCAGCCAGACCUGUCUCCAGGAAUGUCUGAAACUCCAUUAACAGGAGAGAAGCUGCAGCAGCCAGACCUGUCUCCAGGACUGUCUGAAACUCCAUUAACAGGAGAGAAGCUGCAGCAGCCAGACCUGUCUCCAGGACUGUCUGAAACUCCAUUAACAGGAGAGAAGCUGCAGCAGCCAGACCUGUCUCCAGGAAUGUCUGAAACUCCAUUAACAGGAGAGAAGCUGCAGCAGCCAGACCUGUCUCCAGGACUGUCUGAAACUCCAUUAACAGGAGAGAAGCUGCAGCAGCCAGACCUGUCUCCAGGACUGUCUGAAACUCCAUUAACAGGAGAGAAGCUGCAGCUUGGCUGUCAGGCAGGCUGAUCCGGGCCUCCCGGGAUGUGUGUGUGGGAGCCGGCGGGUCUAAGCUGGACUCCCGUAGGCCUGCGGUGGAGUGAAGCGGCCCAGCAGUGCGCACCUUCCCGGCCGGCCCCCCUCGCCCAGGCCCCCCGGAAUUCGGCCAGCGGUGGCCGCCCCACGCCGCUCGCAGCUCACCUACCACGUGGCGCCCGCCGCGCUCCCCGCCAGCCCGCGCUGCCCCGCACAGCUCGCUCCAGCUCAGCCGGACCCGGCCUCGGGCGCCCUCGAUCCUCACCCCGUGAGGAGAAGUUUCAACAUUCGUGUAAACUUGGCCGGCCACGCUCGGAUGCCAUAGGCUGAGCUUUCACCGGCGAGGUCUCCCUCCGGCUGCAGUGACACCACCCCCGCCGCACUCAGCUGUUCCGCAUUCCCUGUUUUCUUAAUGAAAACAGGAAACCGGUAUCUUCUGAAAAUGUGUGUUCUUCACUCCCGCUUUGCCAGCUGAUUUUUAAAUAAAGCUAGCACUUUAAGCAUCUCUA